CUUCUCCGCCUCCGCCUCCUCCCGACGCCGGCGCCGCUUUCUGGAAGGUUCGUGAAGGCAGUGAGGGCUUACCGUUAUUACACUGCGGCCGGCCAGAAUCCGGGUCCAUCCGUCCUUCCCGAGCCAACCCAGACACAGCGGAGUUUGCCAUGCCCGAGAAUGUGGCACCCCGGAGCGGGGCGACUGCCGGGGCUGCCGGCGGCCGCGGGAAAGGCGCCUAUCAGGACCGCGACAAGCCAGCCCAGAUCCGCUUCAGCAACAUUUCCGCCGCCAAAGCGGUUGCUGAUGCUAUUAGAACAAGCCUUGGACCAAAAGGAAUGGAUAAAAUGAUUCAAGAUGGAAAAGGUGAUGUAACCAUUACAAAUGAUGGUGCUACCAUUCUGAAACAAAUGCAAGUAUUACAUCCAGCAGCCAGAAUGCUGGUGGAGCUGUCUAAGGCUCAAGAUAUAGAAGCAGGAGAUGGCACCACAUCAGUAGUCAUCAUUGCUGGCUCCCUCUUAGAUUCUUGUACCAAGCUUCUUCAGAAAGGGAUUCAUCCAACCAUCAUUUCUGAGUCAUUCCAGAAGGCCCUGGAAAAGGGCAUUGAAAUCUUGACUGACAUGUCUCGACCUGUGGAACUGAGUGACAGAGAAACUUUGUUAAAUAGUGCAACCACUUCACUGAACUCAAAGGUGGUUUCUCAGUAUUCAAGUCUGCUUUCUCCAAUGAGUGUAAAUGCAGUGAUGAAAGUGAUUGACCCAGCCACAGCCACCAGUGUAGAUCUUAGAGAUAUUAAAAUAGUUAAGAAGCUUGGUGGGACAAUUGAUGACUGUGAGUUGGUGGAAGGGCUGGUUCUCACCCAAAAAGUGUCAAAUUCUGGCAUAACCAGAGUUGAAAAGGCCAAGAUUGGGCUUAUUCAGUUUUGCUUAUCUGCUCCCAAAACAGACAUGGAUAAUCAAAUAGUGGUUUCUGACUAUGCCCAGAUGGACCGAGUGCUGCGAGAAGAGAGAGCCUAUAUUUUAAAUUUAGUGAAGCAAAUUAAAAAAACAGGAUGUAAUGUCCUUCUCAUACAGAAAUCUAUUCUAAGAGAUGCUCUUAGUGAUCUUGCAUUACACUUUCUGAAUAAAAUGAAGAUCAUGGUGAUUAAGGAUAUUGAAAGAGAAGACAUUGAAUUCAUUUGUAAGACAAUUGGAACCAAGCCAGUUGCUCAUAUUGACCAAUUUACUGCUGACAUGCUGGGUUCUGCUGAGUUAGCUGAGGAGGUCAAUUUAAAUGGUUCUGGCAAACUGCUCAAGAUUACAGGCUGUGCCAGCCCUGGAAAAACAGUUACAAUUGUUGUUCGUGGUUCUAACAAACUGGUGAUUGAAGAAGCUGAGCGCUCCAUUCAUGAUGCCCUAUGUGUUAUUCGUUGUUUAGUGAAGAAGAGGGCUCUUAUUGCAGGAGGUGGUGCUCCAGAAAUAGAGUUGGCCCUACGAUUAACUGAAUAUUCACGAACACUGAGUGGUAUGGAAUCCUACUGCGUUCGUGCUUUUGCAGAUGCUAUGGAGGUCAUUCCAUCUACACUAGCUGAAAAUGCCGGCCUGAAUCCCAUUUCUACAGUAACAGAACUAAGAAACCGGCAUGCCCAGGGAGAAAAAACUGCAGGCAUUAAUGUCCGAAAGGGUGGUAUUUCCAACAUUUUGGAGGAACUGGUUGUCCAGCCUCUGUUGGUAUCAGUCAGUGCUCUGACUCUUGCAACUGAAACUGUUCGGAGCAUUCUGAAAAUAGAUGAUGUGGUAAACACUCGAUAAUCUGGAUAACUGACUAGCACCAUUAUGAUCACCAGUAUUGUGGCUGGAAUGGAAGAAGAUCACCUUGGUGUUCCUUGUUUGGAAGAUUAUUUCCUCUGAAUUUCUGGGCUUGGUCUUCCAGUUGGCAUUUGCCUGAAGUUGUAUUGAAACAAUUUAAUGAAAAUAUUAAAUAUUUGGUUUCAAAAGGCAGAUUUAUCUUCUCCCAACAUUCUGUUAUUUCUGAUACUUUUGAAAAACUAAUAAAAACUAAUAAAAGAAGCGUAAAAAGUGAGUUUACAUGUUGAGGAAAAAAAUGGCCCAAUAUGCUCAUCACUGAUAAAUGCUCCCUGGCCUUAAAAACUACCAACAUAUAAUAUAUAUGCUGUCUUAAAAGUUAAUGAUCCAAGUGGCACCUCUCUGAACCUACUUUGGCUUGGGAGGCUGCCCAGUUAAAACAAAAAUAAGUUAAUGGUACAGAAAGAGAAUGAAAAAUGAAAGCCUCCUUUUAUCCUAUCAUCCUAAUUCCUUUUCCCAGUAAUAAUGACUGCUGUGUUGGAUUCCUUCUGCAAAUAAAAGUGUAUACAUAUAUGUAGCAAAUCUUACUUAAACAAAAGGGUUUCUUAACUAA